AGGUCCCAUCAUGGCGGCUGAAGAGGCGGAUGUGGAUAUCGAAGGGGACGUGGUAGCGGCGGCGGGGGCACAGCCAGGGAUCUCAUCGACAGUAACUAGAACAAGAGCGGCUACGGACGAGACCUGAGAAGUGGUGAAAAUACAGCAUCAGUUUUACAAAAAGAUCACUAUCUUGAUUCAUCUUGGAGAACAGAGAAUGGCCUUAUUCCUUGGACCUUGGAUAACACCAUCAGUGAAGAGAACAGAGCUGUUAUUGAGAAAAUGUUGUUGGAAGAAGAAUAUUAUUUAUCUAAAAAAUCACAACCGGAAAAAGUCUGGCUUGAUCAAAAGGAAGAUGAUAAAAAAUACAUGAAGAGUCUGCAGAAAACAGCAAAAAUCAUGGUACACUCUCCUACAAAACCAGCCAGUUACUCAGUAAAGUGGACGAUAGAAGAAAAAGAGCUGUUUGAACAAGGGCUGGCUAAAUUUGGCCGAAGAUGGACCAAAAUUUCAAAGCUAAUUGGAAGCCGCACUGUUUUACAAGUGAAGAGUUAUGCAAGACAGUAUUUUAAAAAUAAGGUCAAAUGCGGUCUGGAUAAAGAAACACCAAAUCAGAAGACCGGCCAUAAUCUUCAAGUUAAAAAUGAAGAUAAAGGGACAAAGGCAUGGACACCAUCAUGUUUAAGGGGACGUGCUGAUCCCAACUUGAAUGCUGUAAAAAUUGAAAAGUUAUCUGAUGAUGAAGAAGUAGACAUCACAGAUGAGGUGGACGAGUUGUCUUCUCAAACACCCCAGAAGAAUUCUAGCAGUGAUCUCUUGUUAGACUUUCCUAAUAGUAAAAUGCAUGAAACCAAUCAAGGAGAAUUCAUUACUUCUGACAGCCAGGAAGCUCUCUUUUCUAAGUCUUCCAGGGGCUGUCUUCAAAAUGAAAAGCAAGAUGAAACACUUUCAAGCUCAGAAAUUACACUGUGGACUGAGAAACAGAGCAAUGGUGACAAAAAAUCAAUUGAAUUAAAUGACCAGAAAUUUAAUGAAUUGAUUAAAAACUGCAACAAGCAUGAUGGAAGGGGAAUAAUAGUUGAUGCCAGGCAGUUGCCUUCUCCAGAGCCUUGUGAAAUUCAGAAAAAUUUGAAUGAUAAUGAAAUGCUUUUUCAUUCUUGCCAAAUGGUAGAGGAAAGCCAUGAGGAAGAAGAGCUUAAGCCACCAGAACAGGAAAUAGAAAUAGAUAGAAAUAUCAUUCAAGAAGAAGAAAAACAAGCAAUUCCUGAGUUUUUUGAGGGGCGCCAAGCUAAAACACCAGAACGCUAUUUGAAAAUUAGAAAUUAUAUUUUGGAUCAAUGGGAGAUAUGCAAACCAAAAUACUUAAAUAAGACCUCAGUACGUCCUGGCCUGAAGAACUGUGGAGAUGUUAAUUGUAUUGGACGGAUUCAUACAUACCUCGAAUUGAUAGGAGCAAUCAAUUUUGGAUGUGAACAGGCUGUGUAUAAUAGGCCACAAACAGUUGACAAAGUACGAAUCAGAGACAGAAAAGAUGCAGUAGAAGCAUACCAACUUGCCCAGCGUCUGCAGUCUAUGCGUACAAGGAGACGUAGGGUCCGAGACCCAUGGGGAAACUGGUGUGAUGCAAAGGACUUAGAAGGACAAACGUUUGAGCAUCUCUCUGCUGAGGAGUUGGCAAAAAGAAGAGAAGAGGAAAAAGGCAGACCUGUUAAAUCUUUAAAAGUGCCAAGACCAACAAAAAGCUCGUUUGAUCCCUUCCAACUGAUACCUUGUAAUUUUUUUAGUGAAGAAAAGCAGGAGCCAUUUCAGGUGAAAGUGGCUUCAGAAGCACUUUUAAUAAUGGAUUUGCAUGCUCAUGUUUCUAUGGCAGAAGUGAUUGGUCUGUUAGGAGGAAGAUACUCAGAAGUUGAUAAAGUAGUUGAAGUCUGUGCAGCAGAACCAUGUAACAGUCUGAGUACAGGACUACAGUGUGAGAUGGAUCCUGUAUCACAAACACAGGCCUCAGAAACCUUGGCUGUUAGAGGCUUCAGUGUUAUUGGAUGGUAUCAUUCUCAUCCUGCUUUUGAUCCUAAUCCUUCCUUACGAGAUAUUGACACACAAGCUAAAUACCAGAGUUACUUCUCCAGAGGAGGUGCAAAGUUCAUUGGGAUGAUUGUUAGUCCCUAUAAUCGAAAUAAUCCCUUACCAUAUUCUCAGAUUACCUGCCUGGUUAUAAGUGAGGAAAUUAGCCCAGAUGGCUCUUAUCGCUUACCUUACAAAUUUGAAGUACAGCAGAUGUUAGAAGAACCUCAGUGGGGAUUAGUAUUUGAAAAGACAAGAUGGAUAAUAGAAAAAUACAGGCUCUCCCAUAGCAGCGUCCCCAUGGAUAAAAUCUUUCGCCGGGAUUCUGACCUGACUUGUUUGCAGAAACUUUUGGAGUGUAUGAGGAAGACUCUGAGCAAAGUGACCAAUUGCUUUAUGGCUGAAGAAUUCUUGACUGAAAUAGAAAAUUUGUUCCUUUCCAAUUAUAAAAGCAACCAAGAGAAUGGAGUAACCGAAGAGAACUGUACAAAGGAAUUGUUAAUGUGAUUAUUUUAAAGUUAAGACAUUUUAAUCUUGACACAGUAGAUCUUACUUUCAAAGUUAUAAACUUGAAGUGAUUGUAGUUAACAUUGGCACAGCUUUGGUAUUUUUUCUCUAUUUCACAAAAUCCAAACUUUGCCACAUAAAUCAUGUGAAAAGGAAGAGAUACAAAUUUGUUUUCAUAUAGUGAUUAUCAGAGUGUUCUGCAAACCAGGGUCCACCACGGUGUUCUAGUCCUUUACUGAGCAAUGCUGUAGGCUGUGAAACUAAGCAACCUGGUCGGCUUUACUGUUGUGUUCAGCUUGGGAUUUGGACUAUGUCUCUAAGUCAUUUCUUCCCUGAACUAGUCAUUUAUGUUCCAUUGUGGUAUCUCCUAUUUCAUUUAAAAGCACUUCCAUUCUUUCCAUAUAUUCUGCUGAGAUUUGUUUAUGGCUAUAAAUGAGAUAUGGAUGGGUGGUCACUGAGAUAAUUAAUAUGGUUUAGAACUACUGAUUAAUAAAUCUAACAGGAGACCAGGAGAGGCAUGACAAGAAAAUCUUAAAAACAGGAAAAACCCAAAGGAGAGAACUAAAUUACCAGUUUCUAAUCAUAGAUACUAUCUUCCAUUUCAUUGUAUAGCAGUAGUAUCAUAAGAUAUGCCAUUUUCUCAGCUAUCUGAAAAUUUUUAACCAAUUUUACACACAUAAAAUAAUUAGCUUCAAUUGUGAGUCCACUUACAUUAGUAGGUGUGAUAAAACCUCAUUUAACUGGAACAUAGGUAAUCAUAACUCAAACUUUUUUUCUACUGCCUACUACUAGGAGAAAGAGGCAAAUGAUAAUAAAGCUGGAAUAAAUCAGAGAUUUAAUUUUUAAAACAAGCCUUUCAGGACAUGUUACAUAUUCAGCCCAGUUUCAUAUGCUUUCUGAAUCUAUAAUGGAGGUCAGUGAACUUUUUUAAUGUAAAGGGCCAGUUUGUAAAUAAUUUUGGCUUUUCAGGCCACAUAUGAUGUCUAUGAGACAUUCUUCUUUGUGUGUGUGUGUGUGUGUGUGUGUGUGUGUGUGUGUUUUACAGCCCUUUAAAAUGAUAAAAACCAUUGUUAACUCACAGGCCUCAUAAAACAUAGGCUGUUGGCUAUUAUUCUCCAACCCUUGAUCUAGAGAAUUUUAAACAUUAGAAUUUUGUUUUACAUUUGUUAAGCUUUACGUCAUCUUCAAAUGACACCAAAACUCAGAAUUAUGAUCUGCAUUUAAGCCAAUUUUAAAAUAAAAUAAGCAGUCAAUGCUGCCUCAUUUAUUGAAAUUCAGUAGAUUUUAGUUUAUUUCUUAGUAGUCAGAGAAUUGAUUUAUAGCUAUUCACCAAACAUUCUUACUAACGUUUCCUUAUAUCUAAAUCAGAUUGAUUCUAUAUUUUGCUUUGUUUGUAAUCAAUAGCCAAUGAAGAAUAAGGAGUAUUGGAAGAAGCAGUGAGUCAGCUUUAGGUGACCUGGUUCUUGUCUCAACUUUGUGAUUUGGGGAGAUACAGUUUACUUUCCCUGAGCCUUAAUUCUUGUGUAACUGAAGUCUAACUUAACUUCUUAAUGUCCUUCCAGAACUAAAAUUUUAUUGUUCAUUCUAAUCGUUGGACUACUCUUGUGAAGUUUAUAUUUUGAGUUAAUACAGUUUCCAAAUUAACAUACAUUUAAAAAAAAAAGGGUAGUAUUUUUCCAUUUCUCUGUGUGCACUUAGGAUAAACAGUGAAGUAUAGCUUAUAAAACAAUUAGUUUGAGGGCUGAGAGUGUAAGAGGAACUAUACCAAAAGUCAGGAAACCUGAGCUCUUACCCUAACUCUGUUACCAACUUUGCUGUGUGACCUUAAUCAAAACACAUAACCUGGACCCCAUGCUCCUCACCAGUAAAUCAAGGGCCUGAAUUUUAUGGCUUAGUAUUCCCUUCCAAGCUCCGAAGUUGCGUGAUUCUGUGAAAGGCAGUGAUUGAUUCCUUUGUACUCAUCUUCCUUUUGACCUGUUUCCUCAUGAUAUAUUGGGGAACAAAUACUAAAAAGUGUUUUAUACUAGCUUUCUUGAUUGACAUUUCCCUAUAAUACUGAUGAAUUUGGGUGAUGGAAAGUAAUGGAAAUUGUUAAAAGUUCUGCUCUCAAAUCUGAGUCUCCUUGCCCUGUGUGCCAAUGUUUAACCAUAUUUGCUAAUCUAAGCCAUAUUGCGAGGAUCUCAAGGAUGAUACUUGUCAAGAGUUUGGGGCCUUGAGAGCACAGUUUUCAAAAUAAUACUUAGUAUUUUCUGACUAUAGAGUACAUUUGUCUUGUAAAGUAUAUUUUAAAAUACAGAGAAGUGUGAAGUACAAAUAUCUCAGUGCUACUAUUUAAAAAAACACAAUUAGUAUAUAAAUCCUUCCCCAUUUUUUUGACAGUAUAAUUUUAGUAUGUUAAACUUGGUUACUUCUUUCUCUCUUCCUCCAUCAUUUUCCCUGCUUCCUUUUUCUUUUGUCAUAUUCUUAAAACAAUUUUGCAACCACAGGUACCCACAUUGCUGGCACUACCAGCCUUGGGCUACUACCGAGGAUAAUGGAGCCAGGGCCUUGUAGAAGCACAGAGGAAGUCUAGAACUGAGGGGGCCUAUGAUACAGGAAGUUCAGGAGGCAGAGUCUCAAAGGAACACCUGCCUUUAAUAAUGUUUACAGAAGUGGAGAAAGGACUAAAGGACUUAAAGACAUGCAGGUGUCUUCAUCCUGAUUCUGUCUUUGUUAUUGCACAAUGACUAUAAAAUAAUGACCUAAUUUUUUUUUUUUUCUGGCUUGGCUAAUGGAAAUCGACACUAGCGCUUCCCCAGUAUUAGACUUAAUCUAAUUCCAAAGUAACAUUCAAGAAAAGAAAAACCAGUGGAACAGGAUCAGUAAGCUCAGACUCUCCAUCUCCAUUAUUUUAGCCUUGACCAUUCUUCUCUAAUCCUUUUAAAUUAUCUUCAGUUUCCAGUUCAAGUUACAUUGCUUCAGUUACAGUUUGUUUGACCCUGUAUUCAGAGCUGCAUUAUGAUUCUUGUGGGCCCUAGAUAGUUUUGCCAUCUUAGACCCCUUCUUCCAUACAAAAUUAAAAGUGAUAUUUUACAAUUGUAUCUGUAUGAAAUGAAUGUAUUAAUAUUUUAGAUUAAAACAUUUUGUUUAGAAGUUCAGUUUUUUCUUAUGAGGCUAAAAAAAAUUAAAACAUUUUUGUGGGCUUCUAAAAAACUGUGGGCCUUAGGUACUGUGCCUAAUGGAUAAGUUGGCAUUGCCUGUAUUCUGAAGGGCAUCAUUGGAAAAAUAGCAGUCAUUAUUCUGUCCCCUUCUCCCACCACCACAGUCCUUGGAGAAGCCUUUGCCACUCCAUCCAGGAGCACUGCAGUUUCCACGGUUAUAGAUCUAUAGACUUGAACUUACUUCCUUCCCAACCUAACGAAAACUCACAAGGAUUACUUGGGACCAUUCAUCCUCAAAAAAGAUAGGAGGCAGUGGUUUGUUUUAGUCUUCAGAUAUUUUUGUUUUGGUCAGUCCCUAAUCUGUAGUUUUGAAACUCGUGCCACACUUGAAAGGGAAACAUCCUACUACCUUUCUUUCCUCUCCAUUUCCCACAAACCCUUUCCUUCAUCAUCACUCCCUGCAUUCUUACUUCUCAGCAUAUAAAUACAAGACCCUUCUUUCUAUUAUUUGUUGAAAGCUAGGCCUGUAAAAUAGAGAUGGACAGACCAUGCAUGUUUCCAUGAAGCUAUUUAAUGCUGCUCCCAGUCUUCUGUCCAUACCAUUCCUUCCCUGCCCCUAGGAGUGGGGUUGAGGUCUGUGACAUGCAGACUGUAAGCACAGUCAGAACCUCUGCAGCUCUCAACCCAACAGAGGAGACUGUGGCUUCAACAUGCCAACCUGAGCAGGUCUCCUCUGCAUUACCUUCCUCCCAUUUCUCUUCCUGGGUCCUGAUGAGGUGAGCUGGAGGAACCAAUAGUCAGGAUGCCCUGGAAUUGAUGUUGCUCUGUUUUGUGCUCACAAAACAGCCAUGUAACACAUGAGCACCUGAGUUGAAGCCAUCCAGUCGCAAGUCAGCAGACAGCAGUUGAUGGAAUUCUCAGUAGAAAUUCAGUAAGGGUGCCCAAAUUUUAUUUUUUUUUUCACCUAUACUCUACCAAUAUAUGGUAUUUAGGAAAACUUCUUUUAUCCAAGCACAAAGAAAAGCACACACAUUUUUAUAAUCAUCUGCUUCAUCAGGGUAAAUAAAUAAUUUAACAAAUUUGAUCAGCAUCUCUAGUUUACCAGUACUUUAAUAUUAGUUUUCUUACAAAUUAAUGUAUUUUGCAAUAUUUCCAGAAAAUCACUGUGGGAGAAUAAUGUAAUAUACUUUAGGAUAUAUUUCCUGACCUUUUCUUAAAUGGCUUCAUGUGCUAUUCCCCCAAAUUCUGCUUUCUCUAUUUUCUUUUUUAUUUAACCUAUAAUUAUACUUUCUAGUAUAUUCUGAGUCUAUCUUCUAAGCCACCUUACAUUUUUCCUGGAACAAGGGAGGGAAUAAAUAGUUGCCUCCACUAAAUCAGGAAAAAAUAAAAAUAUCCCAGGGGAGCUGUGAUUAUGCCAAGAGCUCUAAACAGAAGUUUGAGAAGGUAAAAAUUAAGUUGUAGUAUCUGAGUUGUUUUUAUUUUCUUCCUUUGGUGUUUAUGAAGGUAUUCAUAAGAACUUUAAUUUCAGGGGAAAAAAAUGCCUGAUUUGCUAUUUUUGACAUUUCCUCGUCUCUUAAGAAGUCAGUUAAAUAUGUUUUCAUAGUUUAUAUUCCUGUUUCAUAGAUUACUGUGAAACAUGUAUUUAAACCUAUGAAUUAUAAAAUAGUAUUUAGAUUCUAGCGUGAGUUAAAUAGAUUAGUCAUAUAUCUUUUAGAUUUGUGGAUUUGACAUGUAAAUUAUGUGUUGUGUAUAAGUAAGUUAGUUACUAAACAUAUGGCAUGGUUAUUGAUAAACUUGUUGCUAUUUUUUUCCAAAUGCUAUCAGUGUUUGUGGACUUUUAAAAAUUAGUUUGAAUUUUGGAAUGUUCUGUGAUAAAAUGUAAUUUCAACUAUUUUGUACAUUUAAAUAUGCCAUGUUGUAUAUGUCUGUAUUUAAAAAUGUUGUAAAUACCUGCAUUUUAAGAAUUAUGAAAGAUUUUCCUCAAAAAUGACAGAACUCUCCAUACUUAAUUGUGACACAUUAUAAGAUAUCUGAUUUUAAGCUUUUGGAUUUUGUUCUAAAAAUUAAGUUUAAACAUGCUGAAAAUUCCAUAAAAAUAAAAUUUUGAAAAUAAA